UGUAGUAGCAAUUUUAUUGAUUUAUUUUAUAAUGCUCCUUUGAAAAUUAACAAAAGUAAAGCCCACAUAUGGUCCCAAAUUUGUCGACAAUCUUCCUGAACACCAAUGUAAGAAGAGAAAUAUGAAAAGUUGUUCAGUUUUCAUUAUCAGAAUGGAGAAAUUAUACCAGCUCUUUACUGCAAAGAAAUGUUUUAUUAGUAUCAACUGUACAAGUAAAUUCAGUUAUCACGUGGCAACUUAAAAUAGGGAGCACUAUAUUAUAUAAUAGCAUCAUCAACAGUUUUACAAGGGUAAUAAGCAUAAGUUUUAAAUGUGUGCCAACAACACAUGCACACUUCAACAAACACACUGCGAAGAAUCAUUCUGAAAAGUAAAACUGAUUGAAUCCCAACAUUUCAUUCUCACGUAAUUUAUCAAAGUAUGUUCCUGAGUUAUUUUUUUUUCUAAUCCCCUAAAUUCAAAGUUAAAUGAAAACCCCGGUAACCUAAACCACUUGUUUGGCAAGUAGAUAUGUUAUGGCUAACCGCAGAUACACCAGAUUGCAGGCAAGCGGGUUUUGAAAAUGCUGAGAUGAUAUAAGUCCUCACAUCAGAAGUACUACUUUAAUAUCAUAGACCAUCUACAUCAUUAUCAGCGACCACAGAGUAAAGUGGGUAACUUAUUGGGAAAGAGAAAAUGGCUGAGUCAGAAUUUCCAUCUGACAGCACAAAUGAUCUGGAGUGAGAGGAAGAGUGAAAAAGCAGGGAAAAGGUAGCAAGGUAGAAACAGAGCAGUCUUUACUUAUAUUGGUUAAACUGUCGAACACAGAUAAAACUUUCCAUAUAAGGUUUAUCUGACUCAGCUACCAUAAAUGAUUUUUAAAAUGCCCGCAAACAUGGACAACCUCAUAAGCUUCCUGUGUUAAAGCCAACAACUGUAUGGAUUGGUGCUUUGAAUCCAAAACCUUUUUUUGCUGGGAGUAACAAAACAGAAGCUACCCAAGAAAAGUUAAGACUUAGACCUUGUCUAUUCUUAGAAGAUGCUGAUGCAGGUAUUAACAGAAAGCACUCAAGUUAAGCUUCCUUUCUUCUCAAGAAACAUCCCAUAACCUCAAAAUGAGCUCAAUCAGGACAUCAUUUAUUCUGAGUGCCCAUCAAAUUGAUUCCUGGGCUCUGUCUUUCUAUUCCCAUCAAGAAGUCACUAAGGUUCUCUUCAAAACUUUAUGUUUUGAAGAUGUGGAUGUGCAUUUGAGGAUGUGAGGAUUUGAGGAUGUGCAUUCCUCACAGUCUAACGCUCAAUGGGACAUAUAUUAGAAUUGGCAUCCUGGCUGGGCAUGGUGGCUCACGCCUGUAAUCCCAGCACUUUGGGAUGCCGAGGUGGGCAGAAUGCCUGAGCUCCCGAGUUCGAGACCAGCCUGGGCAACAGAGUGAAAUCUCGUCUCCACAAAAAUACAAAAAAUUAGCCAGGUGUGGUGGUAUGUGCCUGUAGUCCCAGCUACUCAGGAGGCUGAGGCAGGAGAAUCGCCUGAACCCAGGAGGCAGAGGUUGCAGUGAGCUGAGAUUGUGCUACUGCAAUCCAGCCUGCGUGACAGAGCGAGACUCCGUCUCCAAAACAAACAAACAAACAAACAAAAGGAAAUGACAUCCUUAAGCUGAACCAAAAUCAAUAUGUUCUAUCGAUCCAACAUCGUUCUAUCCUUUAGUGUCACAAAUAAUUGUUUCACACUAUAUAUGGUAGCCGCCAAUCAUAUGUAACUGUUACAUAUAAUAUAAAUUUAAUUUUAAAAAUUCAGAUCUCCUCAGUUUCACUAAUCAUAUUCCUAGUGCUAAAUAGCCAUAUGGGGCUGGUGGCUACUAUUCUGGACAGUACAGAAUACAGAACGUUUGCAUCAUCACAGUUGUUCUAUUAGAUAGGACUGCUCUAGACGAUAAUCACAACGUGACGGUAUGACAGAACUAAUUUAGACAACUGGACCACUCAGUGAACCUGAAUUAGAGACCUCAUAGCAUUUAAAACCAUUUUAACCUUCUGCAUGUGCAUGCAUGCACAAGCAUGUGUGCUUGCAAGCACACUGCAUAAUUCGCUUUGCCAUUUCAGACAUCCAAGGGUCUUGAGUAUAUUACUGGUCUUGUGUCAGCCACUGAUUUAUCUUCAAAGUGCUCGCAUAUUUACAUUUCUCCUAUGCUGCUUCUUCCUCAGGCCUAAUGUGAUAGUUUUGCUAACCUCUGUAGGGUGAAAGGUUAAGAGUUAUCCUACAUUUAUCUAGCAACCACUGUGCAGAUAUAGUCACAGACACAAAGUGAACAAAUUUCUGAUUAGAAAGUAAAGUGAACCAGGUAUUCAACAUAGUUAGAGGAGUUCAAUUCUUGAAAUACAACUGGUACUGAAUAAACCCACCAAAUCUCUAAUACUUUACCAAGCACUUACUGAAGUACCCUGGAUUCUGAUUAACAAAUGUGAACAUUUAUGAAUUUCAACUGGCCCUGAAAGUUAAAUGAGUCACAACUGAAGAAACAUUCUCCUAGAUUUCUUGUCUCCUGUACCUUCUUUAAAAAACAACUGCAUUUUACAUGGUUGCUUUACUUUAGAACAAUUCAGGAAUAUAUGAACUUAGCAACUAAUUACUCUUAAAAUCAUAAAGAUGAGUAAAAAGGAAGCACUUCUGCUGUUUUUAAAUUGUUCAGUUUACUUUUUAAAUGGGUUUAUAAAAUUUCGUAAUUAAACAUAAAGAGAUAACUUAAAAUUAUACUUAGAGAAAGAUUAAACUCUUACACAGUAACUUCUGCAGUACACUGCACAGAACACUGGCUCUUUGAGAUAUUCAGUGAAUAUUUAUUGCACAAGGAAGCAGCAUGGUGUAACCAAGAGAACUCUUACUUUGAUUCCAACCCUAGCUCCAUCACUCACCAACUAAAUAAUCUUAAACAAACUAACAUCACUUAUGUUUACGCCCCUGUAAUAUGAGAGAAAUAAUAGCCAUCAUAAGUACAGUCAUCCCUGGGUAUACGUGAGGGGGACUGGUUCCAGCACCCCCACAGAUACCAAAAUAGGUGCAUACUCACUUCUUGCAGUUGGCCCUGCGGAACUCAGGUAUAUGAAAAGUCCCUCAGUAUACACAGGCCUUGCAUCCCGCCAAGCACUGUUAUUUCUGAUCUACACUUGAUUGAAAAAAAAUCCGUGUAUAAAUGGACCCACACAGUUCAAACCCACACUGUUCAAGGGUCAACUGUACUUGAGCACUGCAGGAUAUUUUAAAGGUACUUAUCAAUUAUUCUCAUGGAGGUAGUCAGACAUUCUACGAAAAAAACAGGCCACUGAUAGUCAUAAGGCAUCCUCAACAGGGUAAAUACCAUUAUAUAAGCAGUAGUAGACAAUUUUUUCAAAACAAUUUUUCACAAAGCAUAUCCAGAUAGUAAGAAUUCAUUUUAUUUUUAUUCCAUGUAUCCCUAAAGAAACUCCAACCUUCUGUUGUUUCACUACUUGAAUGGCACUUUUCCUGGCACUUACACAAGCCCUCAAAUGGUUUGGCAGCCAGUACUCUGUUUGCCUUAGCCUAGAAAGAAAAGCCACCCAUCUCCUUAAACCUCUGUAGGAUAAACCCAGCCAUGCCCAUUAAAACCCAAAGAUCACUUCCAGCCCAGCUUAAGUACAAGUUUACACCAGGGGAAGAAAAACCAUUUUAGUUUAUUGGCUUCAUAUGACAAAAGAGCUUCCUUAAGCACCAGCUACUGCAAGUUCUAUUUAUCCUUUGAGUCAGAUAUUUCCAUUUUCAAAUUCUCUUUUGCAACUAGAUACUUUAGCUAGCACUUUCCUUCCUAUUAGGAGUAGUAAAUUCAUUUCAACUUUAAACGAUUGAGAGCAAUAUUCAAAAUUCCCCAACAACUUUACUUUAGAUAGAGUCAUGGGAUAAACAGGCAUGGUAAAAUAAUCUCUUAAAAUCUUGCUCUCACAAAGCAAACUGCAAUACUGGCAAUUCCAUUCUGAUAACUAUUUGUCAGAACUCUACACACAUUUCUGGAAAUCUUGGAUUACGGAAAUCAAAAGUUAGGAACAGAAAACAAAUGUGUAAAUCUUGAAAUUUCUGCAAUUCCACUGUUAGGCCACCACAGGCUCAGUAACUGGUCAUGUUCACUGACUAAAAAUGUGUUUGUCUAAAAGAUACCUUGAGAUCAUGGGUACAUUCCUAGAAUCAAAUCAGUUUUAUACAACCUAGGAGGAUACUUCCACAGAAGAUCAGGAGCUAUAUCUGCCUAAUUUUAAUAAAAGUAAGCUUACAUAAAAAUAAUAUUUCUUCCCCUAGAAACAAUCUAUACAGAAUAAGGUGACCGCACAGCAGACUUGAGGAAGCCAGCCAGUGUUUCAAAGUACGUCCAGAAAAUUCCCACACAAGUAACAGGGAGUUACACAUAGAUUUUAAGAAGUGAUUCUGUCAACCCUUUGGCUCUCCAUGCAGUUUCACAAGAGUGGGGUAAUUUUUUUUUCAGAAAGAAAUUUAUAUUCACCUUAUUGGUACUUCAGUUACAUGUGAACUCUUGAUAGUUCUCUAUUCCCAACAAAGGCUGAAAACAGCUAGCACUCUGAGAAGAGAAAAGCCAAAACUUAAGCUGCCAGUCACACUGAGAGACUCCAGUGAGGAGGAUGCUAAGACUUCAAUAACAUACAAAUAAACAGAGUAUACAGAGCAACAACCUGGAUCUGUUUUGAAUUUUUUUAAGUGUUUAAGAAGUAUUUGUGAGUAUCUUGAGUACAGAUCAGGACUCAAAUAUUGCUUACUUCCAGGCUAAAAGACCUUGGGCAAGUACUUAAUUUCUUUGAACCUCAGGUUCCUCAUCUGUAAAAUAAGGAUAAAUGUUGUGAGGACUAAAUUAGAUAAGGUAUGUGAAGGGCGAAAGAAAGCAUCUGCUACUCACUAAGCAGCAGCUCAAUAAAUAGAGCCUAUUAUUGGCCUCAUUAAAGUUAAUAAAUUCUUAUAAUUAGUUAUUUUCUAUUAGGUAUUGCUUCUAGUGAGGUCCCACUAAGUCACUGAUUAACAUAGAUCUAGUCACUUGUCUAGUACAGAAUCUGUGCUGCAAUUUACAGUGAGUACUUGCUCUUAGGAAUCUGCAGAAAUGAUCCCAGUGCAGGCUAAGCUGGGAGGAUCACUUGAGGCCAGGAGUUCAAGAUCAGCCUGGGCAAUAUAGUGAGACCCUCACUCUACCAAAAAAAAAAAAAUUAAUUAGCUGGGCCUGUAGUCCUAGCUACUCAGGAGGCUGAGGCAGAAGGAUCACUUGAGCCCAGGAGCUUGAGGCCACAGUGAGCUAUGACUGCACCACUGCACGCCAGCCUGGACAACAGAGUGAAACCCUGUCUCUAGAAGAAAAAGAAAUAGAAUCUGAAGCAAUGUUUCCUGGCAAGGAAUAACAAUAUAAUCAAUAGUUUACUGCACGUCUAAAGCUCUUUCUAACCUCAUAUGUCCGCCUGAGGGAGAAUAUGUUUCCUAUACACAUUGUAGGCCUGAGUUAAGGGGAAAUCAGAAUGUCUAAAAUGUUUAAUAAGCUCCGCCACUCCAAACUUUUUCAGCUGAAUGUCCAAGAUUAGAAAGUAAAGUAGAAUUCUAUGUGAAGAUUAUGUAAUUAUAGUUUACUGAGACAGAAGAAUCAUCAAAUUAUCACCAUCAAGAAGGGUAUGAAGGAAAACUGUUGAGUAGAAGUGUAGCCAGCCAAAAUCUAACCAACAUAUUAACAUGCAGAUUAAAACUUUUUGGCAUAGCUAAAACUAAAUGUAGUUUCCUAAUUCUGUAUUUUGAGUUGCUGUAGUAAAAGCUUUCUGCUAAAUCUCCAUGACACUUUAGCAUCUGAAAUGUAAUAAAUAUAGAUUUACUUGCCCAAUUUACAGAAAUAUAAGGACUUUAUGAUAGUAUAUAAGGCGCAAGCAAAUUAUAGUAUAAAGAGCCCUCUUAAUUACAGAUACCUGUCAGAAUUUUAGUCUUGGCUCUGUCAGCAGCUUGUCAAGUGAAUGAACUUUGACAAGUCACCUUCCAAAUCAGAGCCUCAUGUCCUGACCUGUGAGGAGACAGAUUAAAUUACCUCUUAAGAAUCUAUCCAACUUAAAAAUAAGGUAGAAUGAAAUGUAGUUGAUUUAGUGUAAGUGAUAGACAUUUGUCUUUUGGAUACAAGUAUUAUACAUCAUGUAAAAAUGUAAUAACUGAAGCCUAUUCAUCUAGGGUAAUUGCCAUGCUAACUUUCACCUACACCAAAUAUUGCUUUCUUCAUUGCUGCUGCUGAUUUCACUAUUUCUAGCAUCCAAGAUAACAACAAUCUGCUUAUAUCCAACUGUAUAGUAUCUUUCACCACAAGUACAUUUUAACCUUUUGUUCAACCUGGUGCCUUUUAAAAAGGUGAGCUUUUCCUGUUUCAACUAAUAGUUCUCACAGAGUCUUCAGUAUCAGAGUAAAUGGAGACCAUGUUAUCAGUCACUAACUGUCCAGUGAAUACAAAUGUGGACUGUAACAUUUACUAAAAGGUUUUCCUGGGGCCAGAUGAUCAGAGUACAGCCUGGGAAAGUCAACACUUUCCAUAUUCAGAAAGCUUCUUGAAGAUCACCAAAUUUUUUAUGUUCAUCUGCAACGCGUUCUAAAUGCCCUAGAUUUCUCUAUGAUUGCUACUGAAAUUGGCUUCAGUACAACCUACAGUUUGCUUGGUUAUCAUGUAAUACCCUCUGCAGAGGAAAUGAAAGAAAAUCAGGGGCAGCCUGUAUCUAGGAACAGGAAGACAAGAUUCUGUCCAAAUCCUUUUCUGCUAUAAAGGAAUCACUUGCCUCACUUUUUUUAUAUAGAGUCAAAAUUAUUUAGAUGGUUUAGAAAAUUUUAUAUCAUAACUCCCUUGAAGGAUACAUUUGUUUUUCGUAGCACUGCAUAUUUUUAACCAGUGUUAACUUCUAAUACACCAUAUGAACCUGAAAGAGACCAUUCUAAAAUAAGUACAAAUUGAACAUAUCAUCCCCAAAGCAAAAAGGCUUCAGCUCAUUCUUUUGCUCAUGCUCUCUCCUCUUUUCAAUAUAAACCAUGACAAGUUUGCAAUCUGUAUAUUCAUUGUUUCCAACCCAAAACUUUCAGAUUCUUCACAACUGUCUCCCCUUAUAUCAAGAAUUUUAAAAAUACAUGCUAUGUUUGACUUGUUUAAACUGUGUAAGAGCCUUCCCCCCUUUAUCUAAAAAUAAAUUUAAAAGAGAAAAUAGCACACAUAAAAAUUCUGAUGGAACCCAAUACUAUCUAAGAAACUAACUGAAUACUCUAGUAACAGCAACAAAAUGACCAUAUCACUUUACUGGAACGUGUACAAAAAUUACCAGCAUCUUAUAUAAUUAAAAUUAAUCCUUAAACAAGUAAGACUGUUGCCUCCAAAGGAGACCACUCUGACUUCAGGUGUUGUCAAUCACAACACCAAUCAACUUCUUAUAGAAAUUUGAGAGCUGGAACAACUCAUACAACAAAAAGUAAAAGUAAAAUGAUCUUUCAAAGAUUAGCUCUAUGGAGCUUCAAUGGGGAAACUAUAAAAAGAAGGAAUGAUUUGUGGAUCCACCAAAGACCAAUUUGAAAUAAUGAAGUCUGACCAGAGAAUGCUGGGAAAACAACAGAAGCAAACAUGUUAACUUAGAAUCCAGCAAUCACUGACAGAAUUGAAAAUAUUUUCUAGGAAAAGCCAGAAAGUGAUCUAUAAAUGCAGACAUUGAGAGUGAAUAGCCCUUUCCAAAAGAGCUACCGGCCCAGAUAUUAAGGCAAACUCCAGAUGUACAGAUGGGAAGAACGUGGACCAUUAAGUGAGCCCCUAUCUUUCUCUUUCUUCUACGUCAGGACUCCCAUCUAGACAAAAAGAGUCUUUCACAGUAUUUGUCAACUCUUGUAUUCGAUAUUUACACAGACCUUCAUAAUAUAAAAGAAAAACCUAAUAUUUUCAAAGUAUUUGGUGGGAAGAUGCUACUCAAAAAUUAGUGAAUAUAAUACUUAAAGUCAAUCAUGGACUCCUCCAUAGUCAAUAAACAAAACAGAAUUUGUUGCUGAUGGGGAAGCGGUGAAGAGGGAAAGAUAUCCUUAUAAGUCAUUCAUAGUUUUACUAUAUGCAGUUAAAACUCCUAAAGUUAAUGGAAAAUGACUAAGCCUUUAUGACUCAUUGGAAAAACAAAAGCCAAAAAAGUCCAGGGGAGACUCCCCUGGUAUUUGGUCACUGAGGAGCUGUAUCAGGACUGGAAAUGCUCAUCAGGCAAGAUGAAAAAUUUGGUGAUAAAUUAGCCUAGGUACCUCUGAUACAAGUUUCUAAAAAGAUGAAAUGAUACUUCAUUCACACAAAUAUCUGUAAUAAGUUUUAAACAGGACCAAUAAUAUAAGCUAAAAAAAAAACGUAAGGAAACAUUUUAAGGUGGUUAAAUCUGUUGGAUACUCAUGAACUUCUGAAAGCCCCACAGACCCUUACUCAGAGCUGGCAUACGGCAUACUCUUACUUUACAUAAGAUUUCUACCUACAUUUGAUUUUGAAAGUCCCCAGAAAUUUACCGGAGUGUAAUUUUUUUUUCUUCUUAAAAAAAGAGGCUGGGUGCAGUGGCUAAUGCUUGUAAUCCCAGCACUUUGGGAGGCCGAGAUGGGCGGAUCACGAGGUCAGGAGUUUGAGACCAGCCGGGCCAACACAGUGAAACCCUGUCUCUACUAAAAAUACAAAAAUUAGCUGGGCAUAGUGGCGGGCAACUGUAAUCCCAGCUACUCGGGAGGCUGAGGCAGGAGAAUCGCUCGAGCCUGGGCGUCAGAGCUAGACACCGUCUUAAAAAAAAAAGAGAGAGAGAAAGAAAAAUGAUUUAACUCUGUACUUUUUAAAGUCACUUCAAAAAUUAAAUAGGCUGUCAUAAGAGUUCAAUCAACAAUAAUUCCCAAGGGCAUCAUUAUAUUAAAGCAAAGUUAUGAAAAACAGUGUUUAUACCGAUAACUGAACUGUCCAAAAAAGGUUAAAUAACAAAGUUUUUUAAAAGUUUCAUUGAAAAUGGCUCCAAAACAAAUCUUUUUUUUUUUUCUGUCUAGUAUCAGGUCGCAAAAAAUUUAAGCUUUGCCAAUCACGUGGUCUCUGCUACAACUACUCAUCUCUGCCUCUACAGUAUGUAAGCAGACAAAGACAAUAUGUAAAUGAAUAAGUAUGGCUAUGUUCCAAUAAAACUUUACUUACAGACACUGAAAUUUGAAUUUCAUACAAUUUUCACAUCACAAAACAUUAUUUUUUUUGAAUCAUUAAACACUGUAAAAGCCAUCCUGAGCUACCUUGCUAUACAAAACAAGUGGCAGUAGUUUGCAGGUCCCUGCAACAAAUUUGAAUUACUAGAGAGGAUUACUGCUCAUUCUUUAUCAGAUAAAUGAGCUGUCACUGCAAAAACUUAAGAAAUUAGGAGAAGAUCCUUGUAUUGGGGUGGCCACAGUAUACUCAUUCUGUAAUUUUCCAAAUGUAAUUGCAUAAGUCUGAGUACAUAGUCUGUAUAUAAAAACUACAGAUUCCUGAAACCAUCUCUAAGAGAUUUAGCUAAUAUCAAGUAGGGCUAGGAAGGUGUUUGGAUCCCCAUAUCAUUCUGAUAUUGAACUAAGGUUUUUAAAAGCAUGGACAUGGGCAAACUGUGUAUCUAGUAAGAACUGUAUCCAGAAUAUGUAAAGAACUCCCAAAUUCAAUAAUAAGAAAAUAGUCGAUUUUAAAAUGAGCUAAAAUUUAAAGCAAACACUUCAACAAACAAUAUAAGAAUAGCAAAUCAGCACAAGAAAAAAGGCACAACAUCAUGAGUCAUUAGGGAAAUACAAAUUAAAUCCACAAUAAGAUAUCAUGACACACUUGCUCAAAUGGUUAAAAUUAAAAAAAGUAAAUGGGUCCUGAAAAUAUCAAAUGCCAGCAAGGAUGCAGAACAACUGGAGCUCACAUACAUUGCUGGUGGGAAUACAAAAUGGUACAGCCAUUUUGAAAAACAGUUUGACAAUUUUAACAUGCACUCACCGUAUAACCCAGAAAGUCCAUUCGAGGGAAACAAAAACUUAUGUUCAAAUACACACACAUACAUUAAAAAAAAAAAAAACACUUGUACACAAAUGUUUAGAGUGACUUUACUGUCACCCACCAAAACUGAAAACUCAUAUGUUCUUCAAUUAGUGAAUGGAUAAACAGUAUGUUUGAGGAGACUCAAAAAACUACUUACUAUAUGAUCUUAUUUAUAUAAGAUUUUUGACAAGGCAAAACUACAAGGGCAGAAAACAAAUCAGUGGCUGGUGGGGGCAUGAAACGGGGGUUGAGAAGUUUGGGGGUUAGGAACUGUUCUGUAUCUUGAUUGUUGUGGUGGUUCCAAGACUACACAUUUGUCAAAACUCAGAACUACACACUAAAAAGGAAGGAAUUUUUAUUGUAUGUAAAUUAUUCGCUGAACUUGACUAAAACGACAAAGAAAAAGGAAAGAACCACUGAUAAAUAAACAAGACCGGUAAUACACUGGUUCUGGUUUAUUAGAAAGUCUUUACUGCUUUGUUUUUUUUCCUUUUUCUCAAUGUAGGCUAAAAACUAUCCUAUGCACACACACUUAAUGUAUGUGUGUAUGCUUUUUUAACGAAAUGAUGACAGAAGGAAAUAAUGAUUGUUUUCUGCUUAACAGUCCUUUUAAAAGCAAUAUCUGAGAACUCUUGCGCUGGUUUUUAAAUUCAAACACCUGGAACAUUCUAGAUUCAAACAUCCAAGUAAUCCCCAAAGUCCUUCUAAAUAUAAAAACUAAUUAUCCUUUGUAGGUCUUAUCUAAGAUCUAGGUUAUUCUAAUUUUACAUUUUUGAAGCACAGGACACCUUUAAACGAGUCACCAGUUAAAAACAUUAAUCCAAUGGCACUUCCAGUGGCUACCUCUGAAACAGCAAAUAUAGUUGUUUGAAUGUUUGUUUUCUCCUCUAUGGAUCAAAGCAAUUCACUUCUAAAUAUGCUUCUGUACCUUGGAGAACUGGGAUUUCAAGCAGCAUUUACUUAAGUUUAGUGGUCUCCAUAACUGUUUUCUUUAUGAAUGAAACUCACAUGUUUUUUGUCACUGAGGAAAAAUUUAUUUAUCUCAACAAAAACUGUUAAGUCCCUAACAAGGGCUGAGGAAAGACCAUGGCCUAUGACUUUAUUUCUCCAAUACGUUUAAUUUUAGAGUUUCUACCUUUAAAUAUUAGCCUCUUUAGAAUGAAUAUACCAGAGAAGACAUGCAUUUUUGCAAGACUUUUCAGGUAGAAAAAACAGUGAGGCAAGAGUGUGACUUCCUACAGUUCACUCAGUAAUUCAUUUGCUGAAUCAAAACUAAAAGUUGUAAAAAAUUGUAUGUUAACUCAGCAUCCAUAUGAUACAUUAUCCUUAAAAUAACUAUCCUCAGAAAAAGCCUUAUUAUUUUCAUUCUACUGUCUUAAACAUAUGGCAUAUCACAUAAAUGAAACACAUCAGAAAUGAAUCUUUCGCAUCUACAGAACAAUUUAAAAGAAAGAAGGGGAAGAGAGGGAAGGAGGAAAAGGAAAAGAGAAGGUAGGUAAAAAGAAAUGGAGGGAAGAAUAAGCUGUGUAAGCAACUACUCACAGUUCUAAACUUUUCUAAUUCUAGGCCCCAAUGUGCCAAUUCCUAGCUACUUAGCCUCAGUGGUUUAAUACAACUCACUUGCCCUCCCUGACCCUGGGAUUUUCAUCUGGAAAAUAAGGAAGUUGGCCUAGAACAGUGGUUUUUAGUGCUUUCUACUCUGAAAUCUCUUUUUAAAGUACCAAUUAACUAUGGUUUCCCACGUGUGAGUCGUCCGUUAAGUACCUGUUUAAAAAAUAUAUAUUUUACAAAUUAACAGUUACAUCCAUUUGAAAAUUCCCUUCUUCAUUCAAAAAAGUAAUGCAAGUCUACAUAUGGCAAUAUACUAUUUUCUUCCCUUUUGUGAAAGCCAUUUUUGGUGCACAUAUGAAUUCAGACAGUUCUUUCAACAACUCCAUGCAUUCUAUACCACAGCAAAGAUCAUGUUCAUGUACCAUGGAAAAUUUUUUUUUAUUGUGGAAAUACCCUCAACACAACAUGUGGCACACAGCAGAUAUGCAAAUUAUCUAAGAUUCCUUCCUGCUCCCAAAUUGAGUGAUAUUGCUUUGUACUUAGAACAAAAAAUUAAACCUAUUAUUACUCAAGUAAAAAUCAAAAACACAAAAUAGCAUUUAGAAAAUUUUACUAAAAUUCUAUUCUUAAUGAUUAUCUCCAAAGUCAGAAAAGAAAGCAACAAAUUACUUUCUUUAAUUUUUCUAUGUAAUACAUAUCUAUGUUGAAUGAAUUCUAUUUACAAGACAUACCUAUAAAAAAUUAGAAAAAAAUUCGAAGUUUUUAUAAAUUUAAUGCUGGUAUAAAUAAGUGAUACACACAGUUUAAAAGGUAUUAUCUCUGCCUUUUAAAAGCUUAUACUCUGAAAAAGAAUACAAAAUAAUUAUGCCAGAGACAAGAUUCCUAAACCAACAGAGAAUAAUAAUGUAUUCAUUCAUUCACUCAUUCAUUUAUUCACACAUGCAAAUAUUUACUGAAUAGUUGCUGAUUACAUAAAAGACAUUCAUCCAAAUGAGGGUACAGCAAGAUAACUAAGACAUAAACCUCCUAGCUCCAAGAGAUCCAGCCAGGGUCUCAUUAAAAACCAACAACCAAAACAAAAACUGUUAUGGAAUUUUGAAAAACAGGGAAAGUGGGUUUGCCGUGUAGCCAGAUAUAUGUACAUCUCAUGGACACUGCCAUCUGUUUAGAUGCCUAGUGUGCAUGUGAUAAGCUCUAAAUUUCUUAGACUACUGGGUUCACUGAUGGUACCAGACAUAAUUUUAUAUCUUUCCCCCUUGAAGGUCUGGAUGUACGCCAUUAACUUAAUUUAACACAUUAUGCCACUGGAGUGCCCUGAACCUAAAAUAAAUCAGUGCUUUCUAGGUAUGUUUCCUUUUACAGACAUUUCUAAAAAUGUAUUAAAUUGUAUCUUUCACUAAAGAAAAAGGAUUUGCUCCCAGAAUAGCUAGCUACCUGUACUUCAAGAAGUAAGUCACUCCUAGGUAAACUGAUUUCAGAUGUUAAGCACACACAUGCACACCAACACACACAGAAUUCACCAACUUUGAGACAGUGGAACUUUCCACCUAAAGAAUGUAAGAAUUGAACAUAAAAAUGAGAUUGAGAGAACUGCUGUAAGGAAAGAAAAAUAAAGAUUAACACUUGGAGAAAAUAGGAGAGGUUGAAAGCAUGCACUGCAUGGCUAAAAGUGGUAAAGCUCUAAUGCUUAAGAAAUUGCAAAGAAGUUGAUGAAACGCCAAAAUGUCUAGAAAGGCCUCGAUCAACAUCUUGGUUAGAGAGGGCUAAAUGGCAAAAUUACAGCAAGUGGACAAUUCAUUUACCGAUACAGGAACUUGGAGAGCAAAAGGAAGUAGGGAGUCUUGAUUGCUGGUUCAGAAAAGAAAAAUUCAAUGAAGAAGCUAAAACUGACCCCCUGAAAAAUGUAAGUUUGUCAACUGAUUAAAAGUUUUUUACAAAAAUAUGUUUCCAGCUCUGAACUCCAAGAAACUUUCAGAAUAUUGUUGAAACAUGCCUGUUCCUUUCCCUAACAUUCGCAAAUUGCAUUUUGCAUUUCAGUUAUAGACCUACUGAAGUUUAAAAUGGCUGGAAAUUAUUUCAAAUCUAGAACCUCAAAUGUUUCAGAAGAAAUAGAGUAUUAUUCCUGAAUAUUGGCAACAGCGUUUUCCAUUACAAAAAGUAUACAGAUGUUCCAAACACACUUUUAACCAGAAAAAAUGAUGUGUUGACACUUAGUUGACUUGAUUCUUUUCACCUACAUAUGAACUCAAUCAUUUCCCUUUGUCUCCCAGUUUAAGAGAUUUACCAAGGUAUAAAUACUACCAUAGGUGUAUGUGUGUGUGUUUUUUCAAAAGGUCUGUCCAAAUGAUGAAUAUUUUUGACUUCCUUAAAAACUAAGUAAGCAAGCAUUAGAUUUCAACCUAGGAAAGAAGAUUUUUAAAUAUCCCCUUACCCUAAUGUCAGCUGCUACCCACGACCUCUAUUGAAAUGUUCACGACAAAAGGUCACAGGGUGCCCCAUCCCCUCCUAAACAGCAAUGGAAACGGGCACACACUCACUGCACUAUUCUUCUUAAUCUCUAUUGGAAUCUACCCCAUGAUACCAAAUUGAAUAUAAAUUGUAACUGCAUAUAUAUCUAUCAAAAGUUUAAAUUAAAAAGUAGAGGAGACAGAUACAGGGAUUUUUUUGAAUGGGGUUCAAAAAUCUGCAUCAGAAUAUUAAACUAAUUACUACUACUAACCCUUCUCAAAUGAAGUUGGAGUUUCAAUAUUACCACAGUCUCAAUGUUUGCACAUGUUUUACCCUAUCAGGGGCACAAGCUUCAUUCUCUUUAAUUAGGAUAAAGACACUGUUAGGGAGUAACUGGGCCAUAAUUAAGAGUUAUAUUAGGGAAGGAUACACUUUAUUAGACUUGAAUACUUCUCAGAUCAAAAACUUCACCACCAUUAGUAGGACAUUCCUAGUAUAAUACAUCACUUCCUUUGAUGAUCUUGGAACUAGAAAAGUCAGAUGUUUACAAAGACAGUGAUCUCAUCGAUUCCUGACCACCUUCAAAAUUAAUAUUUAAUUGUAACUUAAUGAAAGAGCCACACUGAAUUUUCUUACCAAUUUACCAGAUUACAUAAAAGAGAUUGCCAAACACCGUAUUACGCAAAAUGAAAGCUAAUUUAAAUGUAUUAGACUCUAGAGUGUGGAAAUGGAAAAAUCUUGCAUUUUUAUAUGGAAGGUGUUUGUGGAACUCCUUGAGAAAUAAUAUGUUAGAAUACAUCAUUCAUGUCUUGGUACGAAAUCAGAAGACCUAAGGGUAAUAUAAAUGUAUAUGAAGAGUUUUAUGUUUUUUCACUCACAUGAAUAGGGGAUUGGAUAAAAUCAUAGCACCAUAUGAUUAAUACUAUACAUACCAGGUUUUGUUUGAACUCCAAUUCUCAUUCUACUCACCAUGCACUACACACUGCACAAGGAUCACUCUUUCUCUAGAGACAAACCCAACACAUACCCACACAAAAAACCCUCAUAUCCAAAAGUAAAGGAUAACCAGACAAUCUCUAAGAUAAGAACUCUCAAAAGUAUGGAUCCGCCUUUCCUAUCGCUCAGCCUCCUUAGUCUUGACAGCAGAGUGAAAACUGUUUUCUACAGGUGAAAGCCCUAAGUCUUCAUCAAAGCCAUACCAGGGACGGAAAGGUAGAAAAGUAUUAACGCUAAAAUCUCACGCCUAAGCUUUAACACCCUUCCGGAACAGUAAGACAGAACUAGGCCCAUCAGAAAUUCUACAUAAAAUCAGUGACCACUAGUCACUAGUCUCCUAGUGCUUGAAACUCUGAGAAAGCAAUCAAGCAGUCCCUCAUUUUCCUGAGAUUUUUGGGCUGGCCUGAGCACACACAAGACCAACGGAGUCAAAUUAAGUUGGCAAUAAAACAAGCGGUUCCAAGAAAGCAAAAACUAUUUUCAAUUCCACAUCUCCAAGACGCCUCAGGCUACAGUAUUCAAUCGAUACAAAUGACAUUCACAACAGAAGCCGAUUUUGCAAAGCCCUUGGAACUUAGGGGUCUGCGUCAGCACUCUGGAACGUCUAUGCUUCCUAGGACCAAAGAAUAAACAAAGAUAACUCAAGGCAUAAGGCGAUCCAGCACCUAAGAUCUCAGCAAAAAAAAGCUAGGUCCUGAGGCAGCUAGUGGAAAAACAAGAGAAGGGAAGUCAAAAGGCUACUUGCUGUCAGCUAAAGCCAGACAACCUCUCCUGUUUCAUCUCCUGGCAACAGAAUGCAUCCUCCUUUUGGGAAACUGCCUCUUUCCCCACUCCUCAGAGAAGCAGAAGGAUCCAAGUCAAAGGAGUUUAUUUGGGAGGAAAUAGCACGAGAGAAUGAUCAUUCGUAACUGAGGCACACUUGCCUUUUGCAACUAAGCUCUACUGAAUUCCAAAGCUAUAGAAAUAUCCAUCUUGACCUGGAAAGUCUGUUUCUUUGCUAGUCCAGAAGGUUUUUUUUAACAUGAACAAGAUCCUCUCAAGCACUGUUUGCUUUGGACUCCUAACUUUGUUAUCCGUGUUGAGUUUUUUACAAUCUGUGCAUGGACGACCAUAUCUUACCCAAGGAAAUGAAAUAUUUCCAGAUAAAAAAUAUACAAAUCGUGAGGAACUAUUGCUGGCUCUACUGAAUAAAAAUUUUGAUUUCCAAAGACCUUUCAACACUGACCUAGCCUUACCUAACAAACUGGAAGAACUUAACCAGCUGGAAAAGCUAAAAGAACAGCUAGUGGAGGAGAAGGAUUCUGAGACGUCCUAUGCUGUAGAUGGUCUAUUCUCUUCUCAUCCUAGCAAACGAGCUUGCUUUUGGAAAUACUGUGUUUAAAGCUUUUUCUCUGGAUGCAAAAAAAGAUAAGAAUAUCAGGAAAAUAUAUGUAUCUACUCACUCUGCUGUAGGCAGACCCCCUGAAACUAUUGCUGUGGAAUAAAAGAUGAAAUGCUCCUGAUUAUUGUAAAUACAAAAUUGCAUGCGGGAUUGUGUAAAGACAAUGCCAGGUUGGACUGCCAGAAUGAGCCAACAGCACUUGCUUCCCCCUGUAGAGAGCCUAUGAAUGGACGUGCAGUCAGGGAGGUUUCAUAUCACCAAGAUUCCUAUCCCAGAAAAGCAGAUGUUCAUAGCUCUGGGAAUGGAAUGCGCCCCUCGUGGAGAGCCUAUAAACGGAUGCAUGGAAGGCGCCUGUCCAUAUGGAUAAGAUAGGGUUGUAAACGUCCUCAUCUUGCCAUGGCUCUUCUAGGCCUCUUUAGGGUUAAGGCAUAUUUCCUUCUGAGAAUUUCUGGUCUAAGCGGUUGUCUAGCUUCAUGUCCUGUUUCCAUGGAUUGUUUGUAACCAGCUUUUGUUACAAUUGUUACUGCUGAUUAAUAUCUUGCUAAUCAUAGGUUAUGGAAAGAUUGUGUUUCUGUUUUAAGGCUCUGUUAGAAAUUACACACACAGUAUAUUGUAAAUUCUUAUCUCUGUAUACUGUACUUCUACAUACAAAUGUACUGUACUUCUACAUACAAAUGUUAUGUUAAAGAAUUACUUCAUCCCCAUGUGACCAUCUCACCUCAUAAUCAAAUGACCCUAAAUCCCUCAUUAACCUACCCCUGCCCUUGCUAAACUUAAUAAUAAAUGCUGGUAUAUCCAGUGCAUUGUUGGCACCAUGGGACCAGAAGGUGGUGACCCCCCUGGACCCAGCUUUCACUAUCUUGUGUGUGUCUGUUAUUUCUCAACCUGCUGAUCCGCCUGGGAACAAAGAGCCCCGUUGCAUUGCGGGCUACUGGCCAGAUCCCGCAAUACUCUGCUAUUUAAAAUUGUAGCUGUUUCAAUCAUAAAGAAACUGGCAUUUAUUAUGCAUAUGAUUUUUUCACCUUGUUCUUGUUACUAAGUCAAUUAUGAUAAGCUUAAGGUUUAUGUUGUGAAUAAUCACUAAUCAGUUGCACUUUUGAAGGUAUGUCACUAUCAAAAUGGUUUUGUAGAGCUAGAGUUGAAAAUGCUGUAUCUAUUGUAUGCUUUCCAUAAAUUCAUUGCUUAUGUAAAGUUUUGUCCUGUUGUGACUAUGCUGUUGAACUAUUAAUUAAAACAUUUUGAAAAGCA